AGCCGCAUGGAUGGCAGCAGCAGGCCUGCCGGGCCCAGCGCGAGCUCCUCUCCACUGUGCACCAUGGUCCAGCGGUGGCUGCUGCUGUCCUGCUGCGGAGCCCUGCUCAGCGCUGGUCUGGCUAACACCUCCUACACCAGCCCAGGCCUCCAGAGGCUGAAGGACUCUCCACAGACAGCCCCGGACAAAGGCCAGUGCUCCACGUGGGGGGCUGGUCACUUCUCCACCUUCGACCACCACGUGUACGACUUCUCGGGGACGUGCAACUACAUCUUCGCGGCCACCUGCAAGGACGCCUUCCCCACCUUCAGUGUCCAGCUGCGGCGAGGCCCAGACGGGAGCAUCUCGCGGAUCAUCGUGGAGCUGGGGGCCUCCGUCGUCACUGUGAGCGAAGCCAUCAUCUCAGUCAAGGACAUCGGGGUCAUCAGCCUGCCCUAUACCAGCAAUGGACUCCAGAUCACACCCUUCGGCCAGAGCGUGCGGCUGGUGGCCAAGCAGCUGGAGCUGGAGCUGGAAGUCGUGUGGGGUCCUGACAGCCACCUCAUGGUUCUGGUGGAGCGGAAGUACAUGGGUCAGAUGUGCGGGCUCUGCGGGAACUUUGACGGGAAGGUGACCAACGAGUUUGUCAGUGAGGAGGGCAAGUUCCUGGAACCCCACAAGUUUGCUGCCCUCCAGAAGCUGGACGACCCCGGCGAGAUCUGCACCUUCCAGGACAUCCCCAGCACCCACGUCCGGCAGGCCCAGCACGCCCGGAUCUGCACCCAGCUGCUGACCCUGGUGGCCCCUGAGUGCAGCGUGUCCAAGGAGCCCUUCGUGCUAAGCUGCCAGGCGGACGUGGCCGCAGCCCCCCAGCCAGGCCCACAGAACAGCAGUUGUGCCACCCUGUCGGAGUACUCCCGCCAGUGCAGCAUGGUGGGCCAGCCGGUCCGCCGCUGGCGGAGCCCCGGCCUGUGCUCCGUGGGUCAGUGCCCGGCCAACCAGGUGUACCAGGAGUGCGGCUCGGCCUGCGUGAAGACCUGCUCCAACCCGCAGCACAGCUGCUCCAGCUCCUGCACCUUCGGGUGCUUCUGCCCGGAAGGUACGGUCCUGAAUGACCUCUCCAAUAACCACACCUGCGUGCCCGUCACCCAGUGCCCCUGUGUGCUCCACGGCGCCAUGUAUGCCCCCGGGGAGGUCACAAUAGCUGCCUGCCAAACCUGCCGGUGCACCCUGGGCCGCUGGGUGUGCACGGAGCGGCCGUGCCCCGGACACUGCUCCCUGGAAGGUGGCUCCUUUGUUACCACAUUUGACGCCAGGCCCUACCGCUUCCACGGCACCUGCACCUACAUCCUCCUCCAGAGCCCCCAGCUUCCCGAGGACGGUGCCCUCAUGGCUGUGUACGACAAGUCCGGCGUCUCACACUCCGAGACCUCCCUGGUGGCUGUGGUCUACCUCUCCAGGCAGGACAAAAUUGUGAUCUCUCAGGACGAGGUGGUCACCAACAACGGAGAAGCCAAGUGGCUGCCAUACAAGACUCGCAACAUCACGGUCUUCAGGCAGACGUCCACCCACCUCCAGAUGGCCACCAGCUUCGGGCUGGAGCUCGUGGUCCAGCUGCGCCCCAUCUUCCAGGCCUAUGUCACUGUUGGGCCCCAGUUCAGAGGUCAGACCAGAGGGCUCUGCGGCAACUUCAACGGGGACACAACGGAUGACUUCACCACUAGCAUGGGUAUCGCCGAGGGCACCGCCUCGCUGUUUGUGGACUCCUGGCGGGCGGGGAACUGUCCGGCCGCUCUGGAGCGUGAGACUGACCCCUGCUCCAUGAGCCAGCUCAACAAGGUGUGUGCAGAGACCCACUGCUCCAUGCUGCUGAGGACAGGCACGGUGUUCGAGAGGUGCCACGCCACAGUGAACCCUGCACCCUUCUACAAGAGGUGCGUGUACCAGGCCUGCAACUACGAGGAGACCUUUCCCCACAUCUGUGCCGCCCUGGGCGACUACGUACACGCCUGCUCCUUGCGGGGCGUCCUGCUCUGGGGCUGGAGAAGCAGUGUGGACAACUGCACCAUCCCCUGCACGGGUAACACCACCUUCAGCUACAACAGCCAAGCCUGUGAGCGCACCUGCCUGUCGCUGUCGGACCGUGCCACCGAGUGCCACCACAGCGCCGUGCCCGUGGACGGUUGCAACUGCCCCGAUGGCACCUACCUGAACCAAAAGGGCGAGUGUGUGCGCAAGGCCCAGUGCCCGUGCAUACUGGAGGGUUACAAGUUCAUCCUGGCCGAGCAGUCCACUGUCAUCAACGGCAUCACCUGCCACUGCAUCAACGGGCGGCUGAGUUGCCCGCAGCGGCCACAGAUGUUCCUGGCCUCCUGCCAGGCCCCUAAGACCUUCAAGUCCUGCAGCCAGUCCUCCGAGAACAAGUUUGGGGCAGCCUGUGCCCCCACAUGCCAGAUGCUGGCCACCGGUGUUGCCUGCGUGCCCACCAAGUGUGAGCCUGGCUGUGUCUGCGCCGAGGGCCUCUACGAGAAUGCCGACGGGCAGUGUGUGCCCCCCGAGGAGUGCCCAUGUGAGUUCUCGGGGGUCUCCUACCCUGGAGGAGCUGAGCUCCACACUGACUGCAGGACCUGCUCCUGCUCAAGGGGGAGGUGGGCCUGUCAGCAGGGCACCCACUGCCCAUCCACCUGCACCCUCUACGGGGAGGGCCACGUCAUCACCUUCGACGGCCAGCGCUUCGUAUUCGACGGCAACUGCGAGUACAUCCUGGCCACGGACGUCUGUGGUGUCAACGACUCACAGCCCACCUUCAAGAUCCUGACAGAGAACGUCAUCUGUGGGAACUCCGGGGUCACAUGCUCACGGGCCAUCAAGAUCUUCCUGGGGGGCCUGUCCGUGGUGCUGGCGGACAGAAACUACACGGUCACCGGGGAGGAGCCCCACGUGCAGCUCGGGGUGACGCCGGGUGCGCUGAGCCUUGUCGUGGACAUCAGCAUCCCCGGGAGGUACAACCUGACGCUCAUCUGGAACAGGCACAUGACCAUCCUCAUCAGGAUCGCCCGUGCCUCCCAGGAUCCCCUCUGCGGCUUGUGUGGCAACUUCAACGGGAACAUGAAGGACGACUUCGAGACGCGCAGCAGGUACGUGGCAUCCAGCGAGCUGGAGUUGGUGAACUCGUGGAAGGAGAGCCCGCUGUGCGGGGACGUGAGCUUCGUGACAGACCCCUGCAGUCUCAAUGCCUUCCGGCGCUCCUGGGCCGAGCGCAAGUGCAGCGUCAUCAACAGCCAGACCUUUGCCACCUGCCACAGCAAGGUAUACCACCUGCCCUACUACGAGGCCUGCGUGCGCGACGCAUGUGGGUGUGACAGUGGCGGGGACUGUGAGUGUCUGUGCGAUGCCGUGGCUGCCUACGCCCAAGCCUGUCUGGACAAGGGUGUGUGCGUGGACUGGAGGACCCCGGCCUUCUGCCCCAUCUACUGCGGCUUCUACAACACGCACACGCAGGACGGCCAUGGCGAGUACCAGUACACACAGGAGGCCAACUGCACGUGGCACUACCAGCCCUGCCUCUGCCCCAGCCAGCCACAGAGCGUCCCAGGCAGCAACAUCGAAGGCUGCUACAACUGCUCCCAGGAUGAGUACUUCGACCACGAGGAGGGGGUGUGCGUGCCCUGCAUGCCGCCCACCACGCCGCAGCCACCCACCACGCCGCAGCUGCCCACCACAGGCUCACGGCCCACGCAAGUCUGGCCCAUGACGGGAACCUCCACCACCAUCGGGCUUCUCAGCUCCACCGGACCCUCACCCAGCUCUAAUCACACCCCUGCCAGCCCCACCCAGACACCCCUCCUUCCAGCCACGCUCACAUCCUCCAAGCCCACAGCCUCCUCGGGAGAACCACCUAGACCAACCACGGCCGUCACCCCACAAGCCACAUCAGGGCUGCCUCCCACAGCCACACUGAGAUCGACAGCCACAAAACCCACAGUGACCCAGGCCACAACCAGGGCCACGGCGUCGACCGCCAGCCCAGCCACGACGUCCACAGCUCAGUCCACAACACGGACCACAAUGACACUACCAACCCCAGCCACAUCAGGGACAAGCCCCACGCUGCCAAAAUCGACCAAUCAGGAACUGCCAGGAACAACGGCCACCCAGACGACAGGCCCACGUCCAACCCCAGCAAGCACCACAGGCCCAACCACCCCACAGCCAGGACAACCCACGAGGCCCACAGCCACAGAGACCACUCAAACAAGAACGACUACUGAAUACACAACGCCCCAAACCCCACACACCACACACUCCCCGCCUACGGCGGGGAGUCCCGUCCCUUCCACAGGUCCUGUCACUGCAACAUCUUUCCAUGCCACCACUACCUAUCCAACCCCAUCACACCCUGAGACCACACUUCCCACUCACGUUCCACCUUUCUCCACCUCCUUGGUGACUCCAAGUACUCACACAGUCAUCACCCCUACCCACGCACAGAUGGCCACAUCUGCCUCCAACCACUCAGCGCCAACAGGUACCAUUCCUCCACCAACAACGCUCAAGGCCACAGGGUCCACCCACACAGCCCCACCAAUAACGCCGACCACCAGUGGGACCAGCCAAGCCCACAGCUCAUUCAGCACAAACAAAACACCUACCUCGCUACAUUCACACACUUCCUCCACACACCAUCCUGAAGUCACCCCAACUUCUACUACCACGAUUACUCCCAACCCCACUAGUACACGCACCAGAACCCCUGUGGCCCACACCAACUCAGCCACCAGCAGCAGGCCACCACCACCCUUCACCACACACUCCCCACCUACAGGGAGCAGUCCCUUCUCUUCCACAGGUCCCAUGACGGCAACAUCCUUCAAGACCACCACUACCUAUCCAACCCCAUCACACCCUCAGACCACACUUCCCACUCACGUUCCACCUUUCUCCACCUCUUUGGUGACUCCAAGUACUCACACAGUCAUCACCCCUACCCAUGCACAGAUGGCCACUUCUGCCUCCAUCCACUCAAUGCCAACAGGCACGAUUCCUCCACCGACAACGCUCAAGGCCACAGGGUCCACCCACACAGCGCCAACAAUGACGCUGACCACCAGCGGGACCAGCCAAGCCCUGAGCUCAUUAAACACAGCCAAAACCUCUACAUCCCUACAUUCACACACUUCCUCCACACACCAUGCUGAAGCCACCUCAACUUCUACCACCAACAUCACCCCCAACCCCACCAGUACAGGAACCCCACCAAUGACAGUGACCACCAGUGGGACCAGCCAAUCCCGAAGCUCAUUUAGCACGGCCAAAACCUCUACAUCCCUACAUUCACACACUUCCUCCACACACCAUCCUGAAGUCACCUCAACUUCUACCACCAGCAUCACCCCCAACCACACCAGUACAGGCACCAGAACCCCUGUGGCCCACACCACGUCGGCCACCAGCAGCAGGCUACCCACACCCUUCACCACACACUCCCCACCUACAGGGACCACUCCCAUCUCUUCCACAGGUCCUGUCACUGCAACAUCCUUCCAGACCACCACUACCUAUCCAACCCCAUCACACCCUCACACCACACUUCCCACUCACGUUCCAUCUUUCUCCACCUCCUUGGUGACUCCAAGUACUCACACGGUCAUCAUCCCUACCCACACACAGAUGGCCACUUCUGCCUCCAUCCACUCAAUGCCAACAGGCACCAUUCCUCCACCGACCACGAUCAAGGCCACAGGGUCCACCCACACAGCCCCACCAAUGACACCGACCACCAGUGGGACCAGCCAAUCCCCAAGCUCAUUUAGCACGGCCAAAACUUCUACAUCCCUACCUUACCACACUUCCUCAACACACCAUCCUGAAGUCACCCCAACUUCUACCACCAACAUCACCCCCAAACACACCAGUACAGGCACCAGAACCCCUGUGGCCCACACCACCUCGGCCAGCAGCAGCAGGCUACCCACACCCUUCACCACACACUCCCCACCUACAGGGAGCAGUCCCUUCUCUUCCACAGGUCCUAUGACUGCAACAUCCUUCCAGACCACCACUACCUAUCCAACCCCAUCACACCCUCAGACCACACUUCCCACUCACGUUCCACCUUUCUCCACCUCCUUGGUGACUCCAAGUACUCACACAGUCAUCAUCACUACCCACACACAGAUGGCCACUUCUGCCUCCAUCCACUCAACGCCAACAGGCACCGUUCCUCCACCAACAACGCUCAAGGCCACAGGGUCCACCCACACAGCCCCACCAAUGACAGUGACCACCAGUGGGACCAGCCAAACCCACAGCUCAUUCAGCACAGCUACAGCCUCUUCUUCCUUCAUAUCCUCCUCGUCUUGGCUGCCUCAGAACUCUAGCUCAAGGCCACCGUCAUCACCUAUCACCACACAACUCCCCCACUUGAGUUCUGCAACCACUCCUGUUUCCACAACUAAUCAGCUGUCCUCCUCAUUUUCUCCCAGUCCUUCUGCCCCCUCUACUGUUUCUUCUUAUGUGCCCUCCUCCCACUCCUCUCCCCAGACUUCAUCGCCUUCUGUUGGCACAUCUUCCUCUUUCGUGUCCGCCCCCGUGCACUCCACAACCCUGAGCUCGGGGUCACACUCCUCAUUGUCCACUCAUCCCACGACUGCAUCAGUGUCUGCAUCUCCUCUUUUUCCUUCUUCUCCAGCUGCCUCUACUACCAUUAGGGCCACUCUCCCCCACACUAUCUCCUCUCCUUUCACCCUCUCUGCUCUACUCCCCAUAUCCACUGUUACCGUGUCUCCCACCCCAUCCAGCCACCUAGCCUCCAGCACCAUUGCAUUUCCGUCCACGCCCAGGACCACGGCCAGCACCCACACCGCCCCUGCCUUCUCCUCUCAGUCCACCACCUCGCGGUCCACUUCUCUCACCACCCGAGUUCCCACAUCAGGCUUUGUGUCACUCACCUCGGGGGUGACGGGUAUCCCCACCUCUCCAGUCACCAACCUUACCACCAGGCACCCUGGUCCCACCUUGUCGCCUACCACACGGUUCCUGACCAGCUCCCUCACUGCCCAUGGAAGCACCCCUGCUUCUGCCCCGGUAUCUUCUCUCGGGACACCUACGCCCACCUCACCCGGGGUCUGCAGUGUGCGGGAGCAGCAGGAGGAGAUCACGUUCAAGGGGUGCAUGGCGAACGUGACGGUAACCCGCUGUGAGGGCGCCUGCAUUUCCGCUGCCAGCUUCAACAUCAUCACCCAGCAGGUGGAUGCCCGCUGCAGCUGCUGCCGCCCCCUCCACUCCUAUGAGCAGCAGCUGGAGCUGCCCUGCCCCGAUCCCAGCACGCCUGGCCGGCGGCUCGUACUCACCCUGCAGGUGUUCAGCCACUGCGUGUGCAGCUCUGUGGCCUGUGGAGACUAGCAGGGUCGCUGCCUGCUCUCCUGGGGCUGAAGGACUGCAGAUGACAGACAGGAAAACACCCACCAGCCCCCUUCCCGCUUGUGCCAGCAGCUGCUUUCCUGGUCACCAGGCCUGGCCCCCAAGUGCCCUGGGCCGUGGCUCCCUGGGGCACCGGUUGGAGAGGGGCUGCCAAGCAGGGGCUCAGACUACCACACUCCUGCAGACCCUGAGCCAGCAGAGAGGGACUGAGGCGGACAGUGGUCACGGACCUCCCAGGCACACAGGGCACUCCCGACCACCCCUGCCCACCGUCCAACACCUCCCAGCCCCUGAACUUGGCCCCAGCCCUGCUGGGCCCAGAACCCUGCAGAUGAAGCCACAGAGCAGGCGCUCGACCAGACCCAUCAGGGGCGAGGAGGGCACGGAAACCUGUGCCGAGAUGGGGGCAAGAGGCCCAGGCAGCCACCAGCACAGAGAAGAGGAGAUCCCCAGAGUCAGGGAGGGCAGAGGGUGGCAGCGAGGGCAGGGCAGCCGCCCCCGCUCCCAGCCAGGCAGAAGGCCCCCACCAGCACCACACCCAUCCCCAGCAGCCUGUCCUUGGGAGAGGGCGUCACCCGGUCAGAGACUCCAAAUAAACCGGUUCUUGUCAAGGCA